AGUGCGCAGGAGACCGCGGUCCGCGCCCGAGCGCGCCCGAGCCGGAGCGGGACCGGGGUCGGUGCACCUAGCGGAUGUGCCCGGCUGCGCGCGCCAGCGCAGCAGCCCGAGCAGCGGCCGCCGCCCGCGCGGCGGGGAUGCCCGGACGCCGGGCCCCGGGGCUGGGCCCCCGGCGGUAACCGGAGCGGGGGGGCCGCGCCCCCCCUCCUCCCCCCUCGCCGGUCCCAGAGCCGCAGCUGCUGCGCCCGCGCGCUCCCGGGGACAUUCUAACCGCCGCCAGGUCCCGCCGCCUCUCGCCCCGCUAUUAAUACCGGCGGCCCGGGAGGGGGGCGCAGCACGCGCCGCGCAGCCAUGGGGAGGCUGCUGGCCUUAGUGGUCGGCGCGGCACUGGUGUCCUCAGCCUGCGGGGGCUGCGUGGAGGUGGACUCGGAGACCGAGGCCGUGUAUGGGAUGACCUUCAAAAUUCUUUGCAUCUCCUGCAAGCGCCGCAGCGAGACCAACGCUGAGACCUUCACCGAGUGGACCUUCCGCCAGAAGGGCACUGAGGAGUUUGUCAAGAUCCUGCGCUAUGAGAAUGAGGUGUUGCAGCUGGAGGAGGAUGAGCGCUUCGAGGGCCGCGUGGUGUGGAAUGGCAGCCGGGGCACCAAAGACCUGCAGGAUCUGUCUAUCUUCAUCACCAAUGUCACCUACAACCACUCGGGCGACUACGAGUGCCACGUCUACCGCCUGCUCUUCUUCGAAAACUACGAGCACAACACCAGCGUCGUCAAGAAGAUCCACAUUGAGGUAGUGGACAAAGGUGAGUCGGGUGCUGCCUGCCCCUUUACCGUCACCCACCGGAGAGCCAGAUGGAGGGACAGAUGGCAGGCAGUGGACAGGACAGGCUGGCUCUGUGCCUGGCCAGCCAACCGCCCACAGCAGCGGGCUGAGGGGGAGGGGAGCAGCCCCUCCUGCCCACUCCAGCUCUGGCCUCUGUUUCUCUCCAGCCCACGGAGAGGUCAAAGCAUGCCUGUCCCCCACAGACGCUCCGGGUACAGAACCCAGCUCUGUCACCUGUGCUGUAUGACCUCUGGCAGGUGCCUUCUGUCUCUGAGCCAAAGGGUUGUCCUGGGCUUGCCCGGGAUAAUAAUCCGAUGUGUUUCUCGGGGUGUGGUUUGAGCCAUUCUUCCAUCAUGGGGUUCAUGAGGAUUGAGCAGCUGCAGGCACACGCCUGGCUUCCAGCAGAGCCUUGCAGGUGGUGGCGAGGGUGGCGGUUCUUACUGUUCGAGUAGCUCAGCCCUGCUGCCCUCUGUGGUGAUGAGGCAAGAGAGCGUGCCACCUAGAGCAGAGUUCCGCACACCCCUCUGCACUCCUGCCCCGGGGGAGCCGCGCUGGCCUGCAGUCUCACUCAACACCUCUGGGGCGGGCCUAGGGGUCCUUUCUAAAGCUCUCAGGUGAGGCAGUGAAGGGCCACAGGUGCGGGGCCCACCCUCUGAGCAGCAAGGGCCUACAGCGCUUUUGAACGUCUCAUCAUUUUGCCUCAGCCACCCUGGACCCCUUUUCUGAGGGAGGUCCGCCCCUUCUCUGAUCCAUCUUCUGCUCAGCAUCAAUUGCAAUUGUCCAGCGCCCUGUGGCCACUGGCUUAGAGUUGGGGAAACAGCCCAGGCCUUGAAGCAGCUACAAGCCGUGGCAGAAAGGUCUCUCAGGGCCACGGCACACACAUCCUCAUGGGCAACACGCACUGCCCAUCUUUUCUGUGAGAUGGGUGCCGGCCUCAGUGCCUUACACGGAGUCCCUUAGUGAAUCCUCUCCCCACCCUCUGGGGUAGGGGCUCUUCCUAUCCCCAUUUUACGGAUGAGAAAACCAAGGCUCAGGGAGGGAAGGUUAUGUGGCCAAGGUCAUGUGAUUGGGAGCUGGACUUGAAUCCAGAGGAGCUUGGGUGACUGUGUUUCUGUUCUUGGCAUGAUUCACUGUACUCUGUGAUCAGCCAGAGCCUGUGGGUUUCUUUUUAUAAUUAGCAUUUUUACGUUUAUUGUCAAAUUGGUGUAGCAGAAUGCAAUUCAGCAGGCAUGUCUGAGCCACUCUGGUGUUUGUCACGAUGCUGGGGGGUGGGGGUCACCCGCAGACAUGGAUGAUGGAGCCCCGCCUGCGGAGUUGCUGUGACAAAGAUGCCUGCGGUACUGGGACUUUACAAAACCUGUGUUAUUGCUCUUGCAAAUCUGCAGAGGUGAGAUGGGGAGAGGGUGGGAGGCUCCAGGGCACUGUUCAGCCACCCAGGUUCUUUCCAUCUUGUUGUUUGGCAGUUGGCCAGGGUGUUGUGUCCUCUGUACGCCGUGACCCAAUAGAGCCUCUUUUUUUUUUUUUUUAAAUUUAGAUUUUUAUUUUUUGAGACGGAGUUUUGCUAUUAUUGCCCAGGCUGGAGUGCAAUGGCGUGAUCUCGGCCCACUGCAACCUCUGCCUCCCAGGUUCAAGUGAUUCUCCUGCUUCAGCCUCCCGAGUAGCUGGGAUUACAGGCAUGUGCCACCAAGCCCAGCUAAUUUUUGUAUUUUUAGUAGAUAUGGAGUUUCCCCACAUUGGCCAGGCUGGUCUCGAACUCCUGACCUUAGGUAAUGAUCCACCUGCCUUGGCCUCCCAAGGUGCUGGGAUUACAGGUGUGAGCCACUGCGCCUGGCCUGAGCCUCUCUUUUUUAGGAUUGCCCACUGUAUGACACUACAUCCCACAGCCUGUGCUAUUACCAGCAUUUACCAUCAUAUGCAGUUCCUUAUGUUGGCCCUGCAGAGUUUGUGUUUUCUGCACUAUCCACCCAGUUCUAGUGUUUUUUACCCACCAUAUGUAGUAUUGCCUUUUAAACAUUACCCACUAUAUUAUAGUAUUUUAUAUUACCCACUAUAGGAUAUUUUAUAUUACACAAUAUAUUUUACUAUCAUAAUAUUGCCAAACACAACAGUUUUUUGUUUUUUGUUAAAGAGACCAAGUCUUGCUCUGUUGCCCAGGCUGGGAUACUGUGGCGUGAUCAUAGCCCACUGCAGCCUCGAACUCCCGAAAUCCAGCGAUCCUUCUGCUUGAGCCUCCCACGUAGCUGGGACUACAGGUGUGAGCCACUACGCCCGGCAAUUUUUUUUUUUUUUGUAGAGACUGGAUCUUGCUAUGUUGCCCAGGAUGGUCUUGAACUCCUGGCCUCAAAUAAUCUUCCCUCCUUAGCCGCCGUAAGUGCCGAGAUUACAGGAGAGAGCCUCCGCGCCUGGCCUACAGUAUUUUUAUUAUAAUCCAUCAUACUAGCGUAUUUUUAACGUUCCCCACCAUGGCGGGUAUUUUUAUUACCCACCAUGCUAUGCUAUAGUAUUUCAAAAAUUAAUCCUAUUGUAGCAUGUAAAAAUAUUCCAUUCUAUACCAUACUAUAUUCAUCAUUACCUCUGAUACUACAGUAUUUUUAACAUGACUCAUUGUGCUAUUGUAUUUUUUCAUUACCCACAAUACCACAAUAUUACUGUAUUUGUUAGCACUGCCUGCCAUUCCUUAUUAUUAUUAUUUUUGCAAUGGAGUCUCGCUCUGUCACCCAGGCAGGCUGGAGUGCAGCAGUACAAUGUCGGCUCACUGCACCUCCCGGGCUCAAGCGAUUCUUCUGCCUCAGCCUCCCAAGUAGGUGGGAUUACAGGUGCACGCCACCAUGCCCAACUAAUUUUUGUACUUGUAGUACAGACGGGGUUUUACCAUGUUGGCCAGGCUGGUCUCGAACUCCUGACCUCAGGUGAUCCACCCACCUCAGCCUCCCAAAGUGCUGUGAUUACAGGCGUAAGUUACCAUGCCCAGCCUAUUAUUAUUAUUAUUAUUAUUAUUAUUAUUAUUUCAAGUUAGAGUCUCACUCUGUCACCCAGGCUGGAGUGCAGUGGCACGAUCUUGGCUCACUGCAGCCUCCAUCCACCUCCCGGGUUCAAGCGAUUCUCCUGCCUCAGCCUCCGAAGUAGCUGGGAUUACAGGCACGCGCCACCACGCCCGGCUAAUUCUUUUGUAUUUUUAGUAGAGACAGGGUUUCGCUAUGUAGACCAGGCUGGUCUCGCACUCCUGGCCUCCAGUGAUUCACCCACCUUGGCCUCCCAGAGUGCUGGAAUGACACGUAUGAGCCACCACACUGACCUUUUUAUUAUUUUUAUCCACCAUCUCGCUGCAAUUUCAGUAUUGCCCAUCGACCUAUAUUGCCUCCUGGUAAUGACCCCUGAGGAAUGAGCCAUGCCAUUUCCAUAGGUGGAGGCGACGGGUCAUGGUGGUGAGAACUUCACUGACCUGGAAGAGGUGGAGAAGAUGCUGGGAAGCUGCUGAGGGCUGCCCACCUGUGUUAGGAGAAGGCAGAUGGGGACCCAUGGGGACAGUAAUACUAUUUUGGAUCCACACAACGGGAGUGGAAAAUGCCUUGAGGCACAGCAGCGUCUGAGGCGGGUGAGAAAUCCGGCCUGCAGAGUCGCGGCUGGCCUUCAGAUCUGCGGGCUGCCUGUGAGAUGCCGUGUUACCUAAAUCCAUUUGGGCACUGAGUUCCAGGAGUGGGGGCAAGAAUUCCGAUGACGGGGCUUUAUCCGGUGCGCAUCCAGCUCAGAGUGGUUCCUGAGACCAGCCACCAUGGGCAGCCAGGAUGUGCUCAUCCUUGAGGCUUUCCGAGGCAUCAAGGAGAUGGUUGGAUAAAGAAUUUAGCACAGAGCUUGACUGAUGGCAGGCGCCCACAACAUGAGACACAUUAAUAAUGUGUGUGGAGGCCAGGUGUAGUGGUUCAUGCCUGUCACCCCAGCACUUUGGGAGGCAGAGGUGGGA